GAUUCAAACUGCUGCUCCUCCGGCUGGCGGGGAUCAGCGCUGGCGCGGCUGCGGCCGCUGCUGCCUACGCGCCAUGGAGCAUCGCAUCGUGGGGCCCGGGCCGUACCGAGCUACCAGGCUGUGGAAUGAGACCGUGGAGCUUUUUCGUGCUAAGAUGCCGUUACGGAAACAUCGCUGUCGUUUCAAGAGCUAUGAGCAUUGUUUCACAGCGGCCGAAGCUGUGGAUUGGCUGCAUGAGCUGCUGAGGUGCAGUCAAAACUUCGGCCCUGAAGUGACCCGCAAACAAACGGUCCAGCUGCUAAAAAAAUUCCUGAAGAAUCACGUUAUUGAAGACAUCAAGGGAAAAUGGGGUGAGGAAGAUUUUGAAGACAAUCGUCACUUAUACAGAUUUCCUCCUUCUUCACCCCUGAAACCAUAUCCAAAGAAGCCCCCAAACCAAAAGGAUGUUAUUAAAUUUCCAGAAUGGAAUGAUCUCCCACCAGGCACUUCACAAGAGAACAUCCCAGUGAGGCCAGUUGUGAUGAAUUCUGAGAUGUGGUACAAGCGUCACAGUAUUGCAAUUGGAGAGGUGCCAGCUUGCCGUCUUGUCCACCGCAGACAGCUGACAGAGGCCAAUGUAGAAGAGAUAUGGAAGUCUAUGACAUUAUCAUACUUACAGAAAAUUCUUGGCCUGGAUUCCUUAGAAGAAGUUUUAGACGUCAAACUUGUCAAUUCGAAGUUCAUCAUCCAUAAUGUAUAUAGUGUUAGCAAGCAGGGAGUUGUUAUUCUUGAUGACAAGUCAAAAGAACUUCCUCAUUGGGUGCUGUCAGCUAUGAAGUGUUUGGCAAAUUGGCCCAACUGUUCUGAUUUGAAGCAGCCUAUGUACUUGGGAUUUGAAAAAGAUGUCUUUAAAACCAUAGCUGAUUACUAUGGUCACUUGAAAGAGCCUCUACUUACAUUUCAUCUUUUUGAUGCUUUUGUCAGUGUACUGGAUCUGGUUUCCACAUGGUCCUUGCAGGGAGCUGGAGAGUCCUCCCCAUCACUUAUGCUCUCCAGAAUCCACUCUGGGUCACAUGAAGUUGACAACGUGUGGGAACAUGUCAUUUCCCUGAGAAGAAAUCUUCCUCAUUUCUGCUGAGAAGAUCCUCAGGAGCAGCUGAUGAGUCUUCGUCGUUACAGCUGCCCUCAUAGAUGAUGUCCAGGGGCUAAUCAUAUUCAUUGAUUCUUGAGGCUGCCAUUGUCUUUCAUGGGACCUUUUCCAAUGCCCAGUAAUGAGGAAGCUGUUCCAAUAUUUCCUCAAUGGGAAGGUUUUCACUUGCUUUUGAGUCUACCUUGACCUCAAAUAAGGUCUCCUCCUCUGACCUGUCAUCUGGAGGCUCCUCCACCAGGUCUUCAGCCUGAGCUUCAAUGAAUUGUUCCCCAGGGUGUAUUCUGUUAUGUGACCAGAUGUGGAUUUUUUUCACCCACUGCUUGGCGUGGGCAGCGGAUCUUCUGGACCACUGAAGACACAUUCUCAUAUUCUCAAGGCAAAAUUCUGAAGAAAUCAUAAAACUGUUCCCACCACAAAAUGUUCUUUGUAGGUGGUUCAUGUCUGAUGCAUUCUUCUAACAUUAUCCACAAUGUAGAGGUAUUUCUGGAGGUUCACACCCUUUCAAUAACAGGAGCACAAUAUUCUGCUAGGUACAGAUGUCUUCAGCAGUAGGAGUUCUUGCGCUCAUUUGUCUUCUGAGAAUAUUGUUGAAAAUUUGAACAUGUCUUUUUGAUUCUCAAAGUCAGCAAGCUGUGGAUCAGCUCCUAAGUGCUAAAGAGCCCACAGUUGCAGAGUUCCUGAGUGGGUUGAGUGCAGUUUCAGUCUGUGGCUGGUUUUUAUUUGUGCUUGCAGAAUUUCUUUCAUGGCAACCAGAGUUUUGGAAACUUCUAAAGGCUUUUCUGCUUCUUUGUUUUGUUUUGUUUUGGUUUUUGGUUAGAAAUGCCUUUCUUUCCAGAACAGCCAUGCUUUUCAGGGCCUGCACAGUGCCUGUUGCAGAUGUGCAAGGCAUCCCAAGAGGAAGCAAAGCCCUCACUGCUUGGUGGGGCCAGGUUGCCUGCUCUUGGUCUCCAUGUCCUCCCUUUCCCCGUCCAAGGCCGUCACUGGCUUGGGCUGCUCCGUUGGUCCUUGCAGCCGUGCCGAGCGCACAUCUCCUGAUAGCUCCUACUCUGGGCAAGGAGCUGACUCGGCAGUGGACAAAUUGAGGCAACCAAAUAAUAAACACAAAUGGAUAGUCAACACAUUUUUUGAAAGAACAUCUGAAAGACAAAAUGGGGAAUGGCGAGUCUGUCUAAUAAACCAUUUUGAGAAAACUGGAUAUUCAUAUAAAGAAGUAUAAAGAGGACUGUUAUGUUGCACAAUACACAAAAAUCAACUCAAAAUAAAUUAAUGACCUAAACUUAAUAUCAGAAAUGAUGAAACUUUUAAAAGAAAACAUAGGGUGAAUGUAUGUUUAGGGAAACUCAAAUUUAUGUUCACAGGUUGCAAAAAGAAAAAUAUGAGAAAAACAUAGAGGAAAAUGAUUCUGCCAAUAAAGUGAGUUGGAAAUAA